GUGUUCCUGGUCUGCGGCAGCCAUGCUGAACUCGUAUGGAGAGGCGAGUGGGGGGGACAGAGUCCAGGACUGCGGGAUAGGAAGCUGGGGAUAUGGACAAGCAGCAGCGUUAUAGCGCUCUGGGUUUCGGGACAUAGGCCUGGGCCAUGCGGCCCCCUUGGCCCCUUGGCGCGACCCCCAGGAACGUUCGGAAAGCUGGUCCUCGUGGCUGGGGGAAAGGCGGGGGGUGGGGGGGAAGCGGGCACGUGACCCCGGUCAGCCAAUCUGGGUGCUGCUGACGUGGCCGCGCGGCCCCGAUGCUCUCCCCACCCCCCCAGCCCGUUCGGGAAGGGAGGGGCUGGGGGCUACGCCCCCUCCCCCAGCACGGCUUCGUUUUCUGGGGGGGGGUUGACACCCCGGAUUACAUACCCCGUACCAAGCCGAGGGCAACUUUGGAGGCCCCCUGGAAGGCUUUAGGAUCCAGAUUCUUCGCUGCUGCUGCCUUACCGCCGAGAACCACCACCCGCCAGGCGUCUUGCGGCCACACCCCUGGCGGGUUCAGGCAGGCUACGCCCACGCGACCCCUCCCGUUUCCCUGCUUUGGCCAAUGGAGGAGCUACGAAUGGCACGACCUGCUCGAGCUUGGCAGUCUCCAGUUGGGCUGUGCAUGGAAGCUUGGGAAGACUUUGUUGGAAGGGGAGGCGGGGAGAGAGUGCUGGAGGCUCUGGGGCGAUGGCUUCCGCACCUCUUCCAACCACCCUCUUUCCCUGGAGUCGGCGGACCACAGCUCAGCCAAUUGGCUUGGAGAUGUGGCGGGUUGCCACUUCCCUGUGGGUCUCUGCGGCACUCUUCUGCCUGGUGACUGACACCUUGGAAAUGAAGUUUAUGACGUCAUCGUUGCGGCUGGCCAAUAGAAAAAGCUCCCGCGGAGAGGUGUUCCUUCCCCUUCGACUCAGCUUCUUCACCCGCGUGAGCGAGCGCGCGCGCGCGGAGGGGGUGGGGAAAAGCUCAAGCAGGGUGGCGCGCAUGAGCGGCGAAGCUCCUCCUCCCCGCCUAUAUAUAAAGGGCUGGCGCGGGGCUCGGCGGCGCCAUUUCGUGCUGGAGUGGAGCAGCCUCUAGAACGAGCUGGAGGAUUCUGCCUACCGAUACAGAGCCUUCGAGUCGUCCGGGGCCGCCAUUACAAUCCACCUCCAUCCGCUUGGAAAUGGCCUUCGUCCCGGCCUAUGACUGGUCCCAGCGGGCAGUACAGACCCCCUAGAAGCCCCUGGAGCUCCCCUUUUUCGGGCCCCGCCCAAUCCUCGGAGUCUGUCCACCCCCUCUACUCCGCCCUCAAGAGGAUUUCAAAGAUGGAGGCGGCGGCUCCCUAAACCACUUUUCGUGUUCAUCCGCCUCCAUCCGAGAUCGAAACGGGACCUCGUCGGCCCCGUAGGGGCCCGACAAGAAGAGGGAAUCCCUGCAGACCAACAGCGGGCUAUAUUGACGACGGUGUCUGAGAUCGGGGACCGUCUUUUGAAGAGUCAGUCCCUCCUUAGUUGCCCGCCUCAGCUGAGGCCGCCGCCAUUUUCUUGCUGUCCGCCGUCUGCAGAGCGCGCCAAGCUGCCCGGAGCUCUCCGAGAGGCCCCAAAGAGACUGCUUUCGUGCCGGCCAGGCAGGGGGUUUGUCGCCUGGAGGCCCAAGAGGAACGGCCUCCCCCCAACUUAGCGGGUUAUGCUGGACCGGGCGGUGAGGGGAACCGAGGCCACCCGGACUUUCCGCGGCUGAGGGCAGCGCCGGUUCCUUGCGGUCAAGAUGCUGCAAAACGUGACUCCCCACAAUAAGCUCCCUGGGGAAGGGAAUGCAGGGUUGCUGGGGCUGGGCCCAGAAGCAGCAGCACCAGGGAAGAGGAUUCGAAAACCCUCUCUCUUGUAUGAGGGCUUUGAGAGCCCCACAAUGGCUUCGGUGCCUGCUUUGCAACUUACCCCUGCCAACCCACCACCCCCGGAGGUGUCCAAUCCCAAAAAGCCAGGACGAGUUACCAACCAGCUGCAAUACCUACACAAGGUAGUGAUGAAGGCUCUGUGGAAACAUCAGUUCGCAUGGCCAUUCCGGCAGCCUGUGGAUGCUGUCAAACUGGGUCUACCGGAUUAUCACAAAAUUAUAAAACAGCCUAUGGACAUGGGUACUAUUAAGAGGAGACUUGAAAACAAUUAUUAUUGGGCUGCUUCAGAGUGUAUGCAAGAUUUUAAUACCAUGUUCACCAACUGUUACAUUUACAACAAGCCCACUGAUGAUAUUGUCCUAAUGGCACAAACGCUGGAAAAGAUAUUCCUACAGAAGGUUGCAUCAAUGCCACAAGAAGAACAAGAGCUGGUAGUGACCAUCCCUAAGAACAGCCACAAGAAGGGGGCCAAGUUGGCAGCGCUCCAGGGCAGUGUUACCAGUGCCCAUCAGGUGCCUGCCGUCUCUUCUGUGUCACACACAGCCCUGUAUACUCCUCCACCUGAGAUACCUACCACUGUCCUCAACAUUCCCCACCCAUCAGUCAUUUCCUCUCCACUUCUCAAGUCCUUGCACUCUGCUGGACCCCCGCUCCUUGCUGUUACUGCAGCUCCUCCAGCCCAGCCCCUUGCCAAGAAAAAAGGCGUAAAGCGGAAAGCAGAUACUACCACCCCUACACCUACAGCCAUCUUGGCUCCUGGUUCUCCAGCUAGCCCUCCUGGGAGUCUUGAGCCUAAGGCAGCACGGCUUCCCCCUAUGCGUAGAGAGAGUGGUCGCCCCAUCAAGCCCCCACGCAAAGACUUGCCUGACUCUCAGCAACAACACCAGAGCUCUAAGAAAGGAAAGCUUUCAGAACAGUUAAAACAUUGCAAUGGCAUUUUGAAGGAGUUACUCUCUAAGAAGCAUGCUGCCUAUGCUUGGCCUUUCUAUAAACCAGUGGAUGCUUCUGCACUUGGCCUGCAUGACUACCAUGACAUCAUUAAGCACCCCAUGGACCUCAGCACUGUCAAGCGGAAGAUGGAGAACCGUGAUUACCGGGAUGCACAGGAGUUUGCUGCUGAUGUACGGCUUAUGUUCUCCAACUGCUAUAAGUACAAUCCCCCAGAUCACGAUGUUGUGGCAAUGGCACGAAAGCUACAGGAUGUAUUUGAGUUCCGUUAUGCCAAGAUGCCAGAUGAACCACUAGAACCAGGGCCUUUACCAGUCUCUACUGCCAUGCCCCCUGGCUUGGCCAAAUCGUCUUCAGAGUCCUCCAGUGAGGAAAGUAGCAGUGAGAGCUCCUCUGAGGAAGAGGAGGAGGAAGAUGAGGAGGACGAGGAGGAAGAAGAGAGUGAAAGCUCAGACUCAGAGGAAGAAAGGGCUCAUCGCUUAGCAGAACUACAGGAACAGCUUCGGGCAGUACAUGAACAACUGGCUGCUCUGUCCCAGGGUCCAAUAUCCAAGCCCAAGAGGAAAAGAGAGAAAAAAGAGAAAAAGAAGAAACGGAAGGCAGAGAAGCAUCGAGGCCGAGCUGGGGCCGAUGAAGAUGACAAGGGGCCUAGGGCACCCCGCCCACCUCAACCUAAGAAGUCCAAGAAAGCAAGUGGCAGUGGGGGUGGCAGUGCUGCUUUAGGCCCUUCUGGCUUUGGACCUUCUGGAGGAAGUGGCACCAAGCUCCCCAAAAAGGCCACAAAGACAGCCCCACCUGCCCUGCCUACAGGUUAUGAUUCAGAGGAGGAGGAAGAGAGCAGGCCCAUGAGUUACGAUGAGAAGCGGCAGCUGAGCCUGGACAUCAACAAAUUACCUGGGGAGAAGCUGGGCCGAGUUGUGCAUAUAAUCCAAGCCAGGGAGCCCUCUUUACGUGAUUCAAACCCAGAAGAGAUUGAGAUUGAUUUUGAAACACUCAAGCCAUCCACACUUAGAGAGCUUGAGCGCUAUGUCCUUUCCUGCCUACGUAAGAAACCCCGGAAGCCCUACACCAUUAAGAAGCCUGUGGGAAAGACAAAGGAGGAACUGGCUUUGGAGAAAAAGCGGGAAUUAGAAAAGCGGUUACAAGAUGUCAGCGGACAGCUCAAUUCUACUAAAAAGCCCCCCAAGAAAGCGAAUGAGAAAACAGAGUCAUCCUCUGCACAGCAAGUAGCAGUGUCACGCCUUAGCGCUUCCAGCUCCAGCUCAGAUUCCAGCUCCUCCUCUUCCUCGUCGUCGUCUUCAGACACCAGUGAUUCAGACUCAGGCUAAGGGGUCAGGCCAGAUGGGGCAGGAAGGCUCCGCAGGACCGGACCCCUAGACCACCCUGCCCCACCUGCCCCUUCCCCCUUUGCUGUGACACUUCUUCAUCUCACCCCCCCCCGCCCCCCUCUAGGAGAGCUGGCUCUGCAGUGGGGGAGGGAUGCAGGGACAUUUACUGAAGGAGGGACAUGGACAAAACAACAUUGAAUUCCCAGCCCCAUUGGGGAGUGAUCUCUUGGACACAGAGCCCCCAUUCAAAAUGGGGCAGGGCAAGGGUGGGAGUGUGCAAAGCCCUGAUCUGGAGUUACCUGAGGCCACAGCUGCCCUAUUCACUUCUAAGGGCCCUGUUUUGAGAUUGUUUGUUCUAAUUUAUUUUAAGCUAGGUAAGGCUGGGGGGAGGGUGGGGCCGUGGUCCCCUCAGCCUCCAUGGGGAGGGAAGAAGGGGGAGCUCUUUUUUUACGUUGAUUUUUUUUUUUCUACUCUGUUUUCCCUUUUUCCUUCCGCUCCAUUUGGGGCCCUGGGGGUUUCAGUCAUCUCCCCAUUUGGUCCCCUGGACUGUCUUUGUUGAUUCUAACUUGUAAAUAAAGAAAAUAUUAUUCAAGUUUUGAGUUACCUUAAUAUUUGCUUUUGUAGUGUUUCAAAAGGAACAUCAUAAGAAUUGUCUUGAUAAUUUUGAGGGAAAUAUUACUGCAGUGAGAAAAGGCAAUAGCUAACCUAUAAUUGGAUUGUCUUAAUUUUUAAACCAGUAGGCUUUUGCUGUGUUUUUAAUAAAGUAAAUAUGACUUUUGUAAA